UUUUUUUUUUGGAGAUUUUUUUUUUUUUAAUUAUACUUUAAGUUCUGGGAUACAUGUGCAGAAUGUGCAGGUUCGUUACACAGGUAUACAUGUGCCAUGGUGGUUUGCUGCACCCAUCAACCCAUCAUCUACAUUAGGUAUUUCUCCUGACGCUAUCCCUCCCCUUCUCCCCCACCCCCCAACAGGCCCUGGUGUGUGAUGUUCCUCUCCCUGUGCCCAUAUGUUCUCAUUGUUCAACUCCCACUUAUGAGUGAGAACAUGCAGUGUUUGGUUUUCUGUUCCUGUGUUAGUUUGCUGAGAAUGAUGGUUUCCAGCUUCAUCCAUGUCCCUGCAAAGGACAUGAACUCACUCUUUUUUAUACUGCAUAGUAUUCCAUGGUCUAUAUGUGCCACAUUUUCUUUAUCCAGUCUAACAUUGAUGGGCAUUUGGGUUAGCUCCAAGUCUUUGCUAUUGUGAAUAGUGCUGCGGUAAACAUACAUGUGCAUGUGUCUUCAUUUUUUUUAUUUUUUAUGAGACGGAGUUUCACUCUUGUUGCCCAGGCUGGAGUGCAAUGGCGCGAUCUUGGCUCACCACAACCUCCACCUCCCAGGUUCAAGUGAUUCUCCUACCUCAGCCUCCCGAGUAGCUGAGAUUACAGGCAUGCACCACCACGCCUGGCUAAUUUUCUAUUUUUAGUAGAGACAGGGUUUCUCUAUGUUGGUCAGGCUGGUAUCAAACUCCCAACCUCAGGUGUUCUGCCCACCUCGGCCUCCCAAAGUGCUGAGAUUACAGGCAUGAGCCACUGUGCCCAGCCAUGUGUCUUUAUAGUGGAAUGAUUUAUAAUCUUUUGGGUAUAUUUACAAGAAAAAAACCAAACAACCCCAUCAGAAAGUGGGCGAAGGAUAUAAACAGACACUUUUCAAAAGAAGACAUUUAUGCAGCCAACAAACAUAUGAAAAAAUGCUCAUCAUCACUGGUCGUCAGAGAAAUGCUAAUCAAAACCACAAUGAAAUACCAUCUCAUGCCAGUUAGAAUGGCAAUCAUUAAAAAUUCAGGAAACAACAGGUGCUGGAGAGGAUGUGGAGAAAUAGGAACGCUUUUACACUGUUGGUGGGAGUGUAAAUUAGUUCAACCAUUGUGGAAGUCAGUGUGGCAGCACCAUUGCUUUUUUACCAUCAGUACAAAUAUCAACACAGUGACAAAGGCAAACGUCUUACUAUUGUUACGAAGAGUUUUGACUUCAUACCUUCCUAAAUUGGAUUCAGGGACCCUCAAAAAUCUGCAGAUGGCCCUUCGCGAAUCGCUGCCUGAGGUACUGUCAGGCCUACGGGAGCUAGAUUCCUGCCUCAUCUGAGCUCCCACUGGCUGGAAAGGGAAAUGUGGAGGAAGCACACCUGCUUCUUACUGCAAGGGGGCUGAGAAGCACUGGCUGGCUGGAUCGUCAGACUUCCAGCUGAAAAACCCAUUACCUUGGAACAAGGGAAGAACAAGAUUUUGGUUUAUUGUUUUAAGUCCAUUGUUUUAUUUUCAUGUGUCCUCUACCUUCAUAAUAUGUUUCUUUCCCCCCUGAGUAGUUGUUCAAUGUAGGAAUGAGAAGACCUGUCUGUACACAGUAAUUACACUUUUACUGCCAGCUCUCCAUUCCUGGUGGGGGUUGGGAGCCUUGAGGAGGUGGCGUGGCUCCAGAAGCCCUCGUAAAAAUCCCUGGGAGGAACACAAAGGCUCUUUAGACAGACCUUUGUAUUAGUCACUAAUUGGGAAGACAAUAUGCAUCAACUCCUUGGAAUAAUUGACGUUUUCAUAGGAUUAAAAGUAAAGAGAUCCUAUGAUCCAGCAAUCCCACUACUGGGUAUGUAUUCAAAGGGAAGGAAAUCAGUAUGUCAAAGAGAUAUCUGCACUCCCAUGUUUAUUGCAGCAACAUUCAAAAUAGCCAAAAUAUGGAAUUAACCUCAGUGUCCAUUGAAUGAAUGGAUAAAGAAAAUGUGGCAUAUAUACACAAUGGAAUCCUAUUUGGCCAUGAAAAAGAAUGAAAUCCUGUCAUUUGUAGAAAUAUGGAUGAACCUGGAGGACAUCAUGUUAAGCAAAAUACACCAAAUACAGAAUGACAAAUACUGUAUGAUCUUAUUCGUGUGGGAUCUAUUUUAAAAAGUUAUCAUAGAAGCAGAGAUUACAGCAGUAGUUACCAGAGAUUGGGAAGGGAGGGUGGGGAGACGUUUGUCAACAAGUGUAAAGUUACAGUUAGAUGGGGGGAAUAAGUUCUGGGGCUCUAUUGCAAAAUAGGGCAACUAUGCUUAACGGUAGGAUAUUGUAUAUUACAAAAUAGAAGAGAGGCUUUUGAGUGGUUUCACCACAAAGAAACAAUUACAUGCAUGAGGUGAUGGAUAUAUGAACUACCCUAAUUUGGUCAUUAUCCAAUAUCUACACGUGUUAAAACAUCAAAUUGUACUCCAUAAGUAUGUACAAUUACAAUGUGUCAAUUAAAAAAUAAAGAGACUGUAUGUAUAUCCAGAUGUGUCUAUUAGGGGUUGUUAAAAUAGAAUUUCCCAUCUUUUCUCUCUUUCUCAUCUGUGGCUUCUACUCGUAAUCUCGCUCUGUGUGACAAAACUGUAUCUUAGUCAUGAAAAACAGUUUAUUUGAAAAUAUUGUUCAGGGAGAUUAGUACCUCGCUCACACACAGAUAGGACAUGGUUCAGAGAGGCUUGGAAUCAGGUCAUUGGCCAACGCUGUCAAUUCUCUUUAUAGUGUUUAUGAGGUUUACGAUGAGCAUCUCAUACAGCAAUGCCUGAAACUACAAGUGGGACUUAUAUUGUGCCUGACAUCAAGAAAAGGGCCAAUAAAUAUUAGUUUACUCUUUGGUUACUUGCCUCUUUUCACUGAUCCACAUUGUUCUUAUUUAUGAGCAAUAUCCUUUAAGCUGCAGCCUCCUAUGUGCUUAGAAGUCUUUUUAAACGUUGAUGACUGAUUAGGAAAAUCAAUACCAAAGAGCAUGAAACCGCAGGGAAGCAUGAUAAGCACUUCUUAAAUAUUGGAAGUAAUUUACGAACUACGGCAUUUUCAAAGAGUCUGGAGUUCUGUGGAGAGAAAGACUCACAAAUGCUUAAAAUCAUUUUUGGAGGCAGAAAGCCAGCAAACUAGAGCCUGGAAGAUUGGGCAAGAGGCAGAAAGACAGAGGGGUCUGAGUAGUUCCGGCAAGGAGAUAGGAAUGAAUAGAACACAAAGAAGUUGGCCUGGGGAGAGCAGGGGAUGCUGGCUGGGAAGAGUGGACUUAGUCGUGCACGGUCACAGUGGUCUGCCAAGCAGGCAGGAGCCUGGAAAUCCAGGCACGGGCAUCUCACCUUCUCAGCUGAAAAUAGGGAGGAGGCAUUUGAACUUUUUUCAUCUGGAGAAUAAUGCAAGGAAAGGGAUGAUAAGGAAAAAUGAUGAUGUUGGAGAAAUGGCUUGGUCCAUGAGCUAUAGGAAAGCAUAGGUUCUUCCCUCCAUCUGGCAGUUCCCUUCCUCCAUCUGCUCACUGACUACAUUCUGUUUGUCCUCUGUCUAUAACUACCCGGCCCCUCCUCAUGGAGCCUUCCCCUCCCACCCCACCCUCCAAGGCUGCUGUGAUUUGAAUGUGUCCCCUCCAGAGUUCAGGUGUUGCCACAUGAUAUUAAGAGGUGGGACCUGCAAGAAGAGAUUAGGCCAUGAGAGCUCCUUCCUCCUUAAUGGGAUUUAGGUCCUUAUAAAAGAGGCUUCACACAGCCUUUGGGUAGCUUGCCCUUCAGCAUUCUGUCAUGUGAGGAUGCUGCAAGAAGACCCUCACAAGACCAAAUGCCAGUGCCUUGAUCUUGGACUAACAGCCUCCAGAACUCUGAGGAAUAAAUUUCUGUUCUUUACAAGUUAGUCUGUGAUAUUCUGUUAUAGCAGCACAAAGUGGACCAAGUGCCUUUUCAUGUACUAUGUCCUUAACCACUUGUGUUUAUUCCUGCUGUAGCAUGUAAUGUAAUUGUUUUGGUUACCCAGGAGAUGCUAAGUUCCCUGAGAAUGGAGAGCUUGUCCAUUGCAUCUUCAUGUCCAGCCCAGUACCUGAUGCAUGGUAGGCACUCAAUUAAUACUUGAAACAAUGUGUGAAUGAGAAGCGUGCAGUAAUAGCACAAAUAGAUUAAGGCCUAGGCAAAUGGGUUGAUAAGUAGUAAGGAAGGGACUGAUGGGGAUCUUGGAAGGUGAGAGCAAGUUGGGUGGGUGGCAGAAUAGUUAAUUAUCACUCUACUGAGUGCAAGGUUUUAUUCUCUGUUAUUUGCUCAUCUUAUUUCUCUCAUUCUACUUUCUCUUAAUUGGGAAUUUAGAAUUAUUAAUGAUUUGUUUGUAGUUGAAAUAUCACUGUCAACAUAUAAAUACUCCAAAGGCAGCUAUAUCCUGUGCUAUUAAUUUCAAGUUAAUUAGAAUUAUUGAAUAAUUUGAGGGUGGCAGUGUAUUAUUAACACUAUUAACGUUGUUUAUAAAUAUAGAGCAAAUUGGGUUUUUAAAAAUUAUUCUCAUUCUUGUUUUUAUUAUUUUUGAUAUGCAAUUUUACAUAUUUUUGGGGUACGGUGUGAUAGUUCAGUACAUGUAUAUAAUGCAUAAAGAUGAAACUAGGGUAAUUAGCCAUCUAUCACCUCAGACAUGUAUUAUUUAUUUGUGUUGGGAGCAUUCAAAACCCACUCUUCCAGCUAAUUGAAAAUACACAAUAAAUUGUUGUUAGUUAUAGGUGCCUGACAGUACUGUAGAGUACUAGGACUGUUCUUCCUUUCUAGCUAUAUUUUGUAUCCACUAACCAGCUUCUGGCUAACCCCCUCCCCUUACCCUGCCCAUCCCCUAGUAACCACUAUUCUAUACUCUACUUCUAUGAGAUCAACUUUUUUAGCUUCUACAUAUGAGUGAGAACCUGAGGUACUUGUCUUUCGGUGCCUGGCUUAUUUCACUUAAAAGUAAUAUCCUCCAAACUCAUUCAUAUUGCUACAAAUGGCAGGAUUUCAUUCCUUUAUAUGACUGAAUAGUAUUUCAUUGUGUAUACAUACCAUUUUUAAAAUCUAUUCAUCUGUUGAUUCCAUAUCUUGGCUAUUGUGAAUAGUGCUACAAUAAACAUGGGAAUGCAGAUAUCUCUUUGACAUACUGAUUUUCUCUCCUUUGGAUAUAUAACCGGUAGUUGGGUUGCUGGAUCAUAUGGUAGUUCUAUUUUUAGUUUGCCCGUGUGUUUUUUGAAAUAAGACCUGUUAAAACUACAUAAACUUGACUUUUUAUUAUCCAGAUAAGACUUGUUCAUUGCGGAAAAAUUAUAGCUAUGACAAUAUGUAAUUUAAUAGUUAAUAUAUGAACAUAAGAAAAAAUAAAAAUCCCCUGAAAUAAUUAUUACUCAGAGAUUACCACUAAGCAAUUUUGGGUAAAUAUAUUGCCAGGCAUUUUUAGUGUGUGUGUCUAAAUAUAUAUCUACUUUAAACGUAAAGUACACUGUAUACCUUCUUGUAACCGGAUCUUAACUUAAAAUAUGAAUGUGCCUGUUAACAUUUCCGUAGCUCAUCUGGUUUUAGCAUAGCGGUAGUGAGCAGUUGCAUGCACCCUUGACAGUAUGCCACAUGACAUACAAGCUGGGCCAUAUUUCUGCUCUUUCUCCAGAGCUGCAGAGGUCAUCUAGACACAGGAAGACACAACCUAGAAAAAUGGGGGAGUUAAUACUACAACUCUCACAAUGGGGGGUGGGAGUUGGUGGAUAAAUGCUGCGGCAUCCCUGUCCUGUGUUGAGACAGUUACAAGAUCCAUGCUAUGUGGUUCUGCAGGGGCUCCCCAUGCAGUUGCCUGCAGCAGUAACCAGCUCAUUCCUGAAAAUUGUGUUGGUUUUUCUCCUUUGUCUAUCUUACUUUCUCCAAAGCAGCUUACAUCCGGGUCUUUAUCUCAGUGACUCUUUCUAGAGAAUCCCAAAUUAAGAAAACGUCAACCCUGUAUUAUUGAACAAUCCGAUUUAUCUUAAUUUUUGUUAUAAAAAGAAUUAUAAUGGAUAUCUAUGUAUAAAUUCCUCUACAUAUGGGUCUAGUUAAUUAUUUUUAAAUAAUAAAUGCUAAGUCAAGGAUAUGUUUUUAAUUUUUAUUGUAAAUAGAAUUAUAAUAGAUAUCUAUGUAUCAGUACCUUUAUAUAUGGAUCUAGUUAAUUUUUUACAAUAAAUGCUGGGUCAAAGAUAUGUACAUUUUAAAGACUCUUGAUAUAUGUUACCAAAUUACCCUUUAGAAAGGUUAUUCCAGUUUGCAGAGUAUUGGUUUUCCUGUAAGUAUAUAAGUGACCUUUGGGUAUGAACCUUUUUAAAUAUUUGUCAGACUCUCAGAUAAAAAAUUCUGUCUAGCUUUAAUCUGUAAUUUUUACAUGUGCUUUUGGUCACAUAUUUUUGUUUGAUGUGUUGCCUGUUUGUAUCUUCUUCCCAUUUUUCUCAUUGGAUAUUUAAAUGUUUUAAUCACUUUUUAUGAACUCUUUACAUAUUAGAAAUAGUAAUCCUUUAUCUGUUGUCAAUCAUUUCUCUAAAAUGUUUUUUGACUAAUUUUGUGCUUCUUAAUAGCCACUGUCACUGGCUUCAUUGUCAGAUUCUACAUUGGCCUGCACAUCUCUCUCCCCGUGUGUUGACAUUCUCACCGUUUCCCUCCCUCUAGGUCUUUCUACCUCUUUGUCAUUCAUCUUUUCUUUUCUAUACCUGGUCUCUUUCUCCCUAAUUCCUGUUCUAAACAUGGAAUUGAUUGGUCUCUUUUACUUUGCAGUGAUUCUUGCUGGGUGUAGAGGAGAGUCCACAUCAGAGAGGUGGUCUUUCAAGCGCCAUAUCCCCAGACUCUUGAGAAUCACAGCGUUCUUACCCUGAGCUGUAGUGUGCAUAGUGUACCACGGUGACUGUUAGAUGUGUGUGGAGACCCUCAGCUGAAAAGAGGCAGAAGUUGAGAACUAUUGGCUGAAAGGCUUAAGAAGCCAUGGAAAUGCCACUCACGUUUUCCAUCUGCUUGUUUCUAUGAUAGAACCCUCUUGGAAAUCCUGUGACCUGAGUGCCCAUCUCCAAAAAACUCUUUCUACCUAUAUAUACUUCACAGAUCUGAAAGUUACUUACUAAAUUGAUUGCAGAAUGUGGUAAAGGCACAUGCUAGACCAGGUCUAGAGGACUAGUAUCCUUUUUAAAGCCUGAUCAAUAUGAAGGACUCUUUAUGUAAUGCCAGGGGGUCAAGUCCAAAUUACAUUUCCACAUCAGGAGAACUUUCAAGGCUAAUGCAGAUGCCACAGGCCUCUAGGGAGGGGUUACUGCUGUGCUUGGUAGAUUUAUAGUCACAUGUCUACUGUCCCAGGAAAGGAGGAAGGGACACCUCUUGCAUUCUGGGAGUGCUCUCGGCUGCUCACCACUAAUCAGGAGUUUCUUCAAGCUGAGAGACUUCUGGCUUCAUUCUUUUCAUCCCAAACACAAUUUAUUUAUAUCUUUGUAAAGUCACAAAAUAUGAAAUAUUUCUUUGUCUUCCGAGUUAUUUUAUAAUGUGUAUCUAAUUAAAAUUGUAGAUUAUCAUCUCAAAUUGAUUUGAUUUAUAUUCAUUUAAAUUAAUAACACAGUUUCUUAAAAGAAUCUUCAAUAUUUAGGUAACAAAUUAAUAUAGAUAUUGAACAUUUAAAAUUACACAUGAAAAGAGAAAUAAGCAAAGAUGUUGAGAGGCAAUCACAGAUCACACUUGCUAUGACUGAGCUUUACAAUUAGAUCUCAGCUUCUCAAAACCAGGGUGGAAAAGUAUUAAUAACAAUGGGGAAACAUAAUUAUCACUUGGCACAAAGAAACAUGCUAAGCAUUAACAGAAAGGAAGUAUUUCCUCCUGCCUUGGACUAAAUUUUGAAGCAAAAAUGUCCUGUGGAACUUAGACAUUGGACUUAGGGUAAACGUUUCCAGUAUAAAUUCAUGGAAGCAUUUUUCUUAUGUUUUUUUUCUUAGAGUAAAUCCUCAAUGUAAGCAAAAGGCAUAAGGUUUAAAUAUAACUCAGUGAGUGUUUUCUCAGAGUAGUUUUAGUGAAAGUAGUGUCAAAGUAGUUUAAGAAUCUAGGUUUUUGGUAUUUUUAAACAUAAUCCAACUACAUAGAGAACAAAUGUCUGUUAGACUAUAUUCCUUGACUCCUAGUUGCAUCAGCUGGGCUUUGUGAAAGCUAGGUAAGAGUUUUCACGGAAAUAGCAAAAGAUGAAAUUUGCCUCAAGAUGCUGAUUUCGAGUAAAUACCCACACACCUUUUACAUCUUUGAUGAGGCAACAAAAUGUGUUUAAUAUGUUUUAUGAUUCUUGUUCUUUUCUUAAAUCAAAAUAGUUAUUAAUUCAAAGAAACUACUGUUUAUUCAGCUGCAGAUGCCUACUGGUUCUUGGAGGGAGAAAAGCACAUGUAUGUAUACCCCCUGGUUGUGGAAUACGAGGCAUUGCUGGUACAACUACCCCUAUCAGCCACUCACAACUGACCUUCACUACUAUUACAUCCUGGAGCUGUCGUUUUAUUGGUCUUUGAUGUUUUCUCAGUUCACUGAUAUCAAAAGAAAGGACUUUGGCAUUAUGUUCCUGCACCACCUUGUAUCUAUUUUCUUGAUUACCUUUUCAUAUGUCAACAAUAUGGCCCGAGUAGGAACGCUGGUCCUUUGUCUUCAUGAUUCAGCUGAUGCUCUUCUGGAGGCUGCCAAAAUGGCAAAUUAUGCCAAGUUUCAGAAAAUGUGUGAUCUCCUGUUUGUUAUGUUUGCCGUGGUUUUUAUCACCACACGACUGGGUAUAUUUCCUCUCUGGGUGUUAAAUACCACAUUAUUUGAAAGCUGGGAGAUCGUUGGACCUUACCCUUCCUGGUGGGUUUUUAACCUACUGCUAUUGCUAGUACAAGGGUUGAACUGCUUCUGGUCUUACUUGAUUGUGAAAAUAGCUUGCAAAGCUGUUUCAAGAGGCAAGGCUGGGAAGUGGAACCCUUUACAUGUGUCCAAGGAUGAUCGAAGUGAUAUUGAGUCUAGCUCAGAUGAGGAGGACUCAGAACCUCCGGGAAAGAAUCCCCACACUGCGACAACCACCAAUGGGACCAGUGGUACCAACGGGUAUCUCCUGACUGGCUCCUGCUCCAUGGAUGAUUAAUUACUCAAAACUACAAGUCCCAAGCAAAGUGAACUAUUUGUUCCUGGAAGUAUUUAAUAAGUUGCAAAUGCAGUUCCUUUCAUAAUAUCUCAGCACCAGAAACAAAAAUUAAGAUUAUCAAAGCAUUUUGAAUAGUGCACUGCCAUGUGUCCUGUCUGUGAAUGAAGAAGAAUUACCAUUCUCUCUUUGUAGGCAUGCUGUAUGUAAUUGACACAAGGGAACAGUAUUUGCAUUUGUACUGUCUUAGAAUAUUAUUUAUUUUUUUGUAUUUGUAAAUCUGUGGACAAAAGAGGGUUUCCUCACUCCUUUUACUCACUGGGCUCAUGACAGUGAAGGAGAUGCUCCAUCUGCUUCUCCCCCUUUCUCUUGCUGUAGUCCAAUGUGCUAUGAGCAUCAGCUUACUUUGUCACUUAGAGCAAGCAAAACCCAGUGCAAGAGUCUCGUUCAGCUCUAAAUAGGUUUGCUUUCUUUUAGUUACAGUGCCCAUUUUGAAAUUGCCUAUACAGUCUUAGUGACCAUUUAAACCGGACGAACUAGGUGUUUAAUUUUCACUCUUCAUGUUCAAUUAGCAGUUCAAAUUAAAGAAGAUGGUUAUUGGAGAACUUUUUUGAAUGGUUUUGUAUUAAAUUGCUUUGAAAUAGAUUUCAUUUCUUGUGCACACAGCCAAGAUUUCUUCAAUGGGUGUGAGCUAGUUGAGGGUUAACCUUGUAGGUUGCAGAGUGUAUUUGUUUGUUUGUUUGUUUUUCUCUGUGAUGAGGUCAGUGCUCUGAUUUUGAAGGAGGAUAUUCACUGAAGCUCAUAGUUAUAAACAAGGAAAUCACUGUUAAGAAUGGGAAUUUGUCCUGUGUUCUGGGAAUAACAUAAAGAGAGCAACUGAUUUCAGCCAGGUUUUGCCACUACCCUAUAAUUAGUGCAGUCUUAUGUUAUAAAAGAAAGAAGUUAACUAUAUUUGGGGACAAAAAAAUAUUUCAAGAGUUGAUAAAGAUUACCUGUGCAGUGCAGAGCACUUUAAUGCAACCAGCUUUCAAGAAAAAGCCCUAUCUAGUACUUGAUGUUGAUGUUUUUAUUUUGCUGAGCAAAAUAAAGCCAAUGGGAGAAAGACUAUUUUACCCUUUGCUUUUCUCCUUAAACGUAAUCCAGAUGACUUUCCUGUUACUAAACACUGAGCAGCAUUACACUACAAUGCUUCUUUGGUUUCCAGGAAUUUUUUUCAAAUGGGGCUGUUUCUGGAAAAAUGAAAAAUUCUAUUGGACAAUGGCAAUAUCAACAAUGAGGAAAAUUACUGAAGAAUAAGUUUCCAUAAGUCUCCUACAUAGCAGUGUUAUUUAUGUACAGAUAAGAAAACCAUAUGUCAGCCAAAGAUUUUAUCUCUUCUUCUAACUUUUAGUAAGAGGAAAAAGGGAUUAUAAAACCCUUCAUAAAUCAAGAAGGCCAUCACUUAGAACGAACCCCAAACAAAAAUGCCAUAAUAUAAAUGUGUGAAUCAGGGCUGUGAAGACAACAGCAGAAAUGCUAACAAGCGUGCAGAAACACCAGAGAGUGCGUAUCCUGCUCAGAACCAUUCACAUUUAAUUCAAUUCUUGGAAAAAAUUAAAGCUUUUUGCCCACAAUUUGCAAUCUGUGGGUUAAUAGUUAAAAGAAUGUUCCCAACCAAAAAAUUCUUACCGUAAUAUUAUAUCUUGCCCUACUUAUUUACAAAAUAAUAUGUUUCUGUUAUGGUCCUUAGUAAUAAUUGAAGAGGCUUAGAAAUACAUCUGCUUGUUUAUUGAGAAAACGAUGCAAAUAAUUCUGCUUUUAGAGCCUUGUUAUUUUAUUUCACAAAACAGGCAUAUGUCUAGGAGUGUAAUUUGUGGAUGGUUGAGUUUGUAAGAACAAUCAUAAAAGGACUUGUUAGUCUCCAGAACAUCUGCUAAAAUGCAAGUAUAUGUAUAAGGUAAUAGCAUAUUACAGCUGAAAAUUUUGAGAAGGUAAAAGUUUCUUAAUUAAAAUAUGAACAUAUUUAGCUUGCUUUAGUGUCUGGGGCAAGUCCUCUCAAUGGCUAAAAUUAACUUUAGAGAUCCAUGUGUUCAGGUUUAGAUCAUAUGACACUCGAGCACAGAAGAAUAAUUUCAAGGAGGUCAUCUUGUAAAUUAAAGGUUUAGAAGAAUUGCAUAAAACGUAGUAAAUGGGGUCUGUCAUUAGCAAAGGCAAAUCUAAGCAAUCAUUUUUCCCCCCAGAAGUUACUUAGAAGGAGAACUGGGAACACUUGGGGUCUCUCUAACUGAUGGCAUUCACUUCACACAGUCGUCUAUGUUAUCCAGAGAUUUUUAUUUCAUUUUACAUUUUAGGGCACAGUUCUUUGGGGCUAAUUAAAAUGGGGUUUGCAGGCUUUUUAUGGUGAAGAAUAAUAUAUCUCUGUCUAUAGCUUUCCCAUGGUAGCCUGAUAAGGCUGAGAGAGAAAAAUAUGUGCAGUAUCUCAUCCUCCCCCUGUACCAGGCCAUAGCUUUGAAGUGUAUUUUGUAAAUUCAACUAUAGGUUAGUCAGAAUGCUGUUUUUCGUUAAUUAACUUAGCCUGUGUUGAUAUCUCCUCCUUCCUGGUCACAUUCAAACCUUCCCAGAGUACAAAGGGGUAUGUAGAAAGGAUUCCAGAAGAAGUAAUACUUUAUUCUCUAAUGUUAAUAGCUUUUCUGGAUCUCUUAGUAGGGGGAAAGUAGAAAAUCGAGUAGAAUUUGGCCUCAGGUCAAUAAAUGAUAUAAAAACAUGUGUUCUAUUUAUGUAUAUAUAUGUAUGUUUCUCCAAAAAGUGAUAAAACCAAAAUAUCACUGACUCAUCCCUACCCAUAUUCUUUUCAUAAAACCCACUCACCAGGUACAAUAGAAACUUCCCUCCUUGUUUGUCAGCCUCCUGUUCAUGUUCCCCACACACCUGAAGGUGGUAGAAUCUUUUCAGCCUCUUAGCCAGUGAGCUAAAUAUGGCUAAGCACAGGUCAUAAGAGCACCUAAGGCCAGCAUAUAAGCCAACUACAGUUCACCUUUCCAAAUUUGGUCCUAUGGAUGUUGAGCAUAGGGAAGCAACUCUCAGUAUUUUGGAUUAUUCAAGUGUAUGUGGUAAAAAUGCAGAUGAUUGCUGCUUUACCCCAGGGUUUAUUAGCAUCCUACUUCUGCUGGGCUGCAUCAUUAUAUAAUGCCACAGGCAUCUAGUCAAGGUAAAGAAGCCAGAAAGGUUAGGCAAGAAGUGAGAUAAAAUCAGAUCACCUUUGAUCAAAAUGGUUGGUGAACCUCCACAUGUCCAGUUCUGUUGCCAAACUUUCCAUUCAGAGUAUUUGGUGGAGUUUGAAUUUGAGCAAACUAAAUGCCUUCAUCUUAGGUAGAAAGGGCCUGAAUCUUCCAUUUUAUAUUCAAACCUCAUUGUUAUUUGGCCUAAGUAAAAAGUCAGAUUUCAUUUCCAUUUACCUGAGUUCGCUUUAAAGAGCUUUUCAAAGAGAGCUUUAUAGACACCCACAAUUGUCCCCAAUCUCUUCAUGAUGUUGCAUUAAUAGUUGUUUUUGUCCCUUUCUUGGAAAUGUUAAUGCCAAAGUUGCCUGAACAUUGGGCGGUUUUCUUAAUUUGAAGUAUAAAAAUUAUAAAGAGUAAUUCCAAAGGUAUUAAAAGAUUGUUUAACAGUAUGUGUGGUGAUGUCAUUAUCUCCAGAGAGGCUUCAAGAAAUCCUUUGGAAAUAAAAAGUUAAAUGUUUACAUUUCAUGUGGUAUUUCAGGUCUUCAGGUUCUGAUUAGCUUACUUUUUUCCUUUGUCUUUGGCUGAUUUCUGCUUUGUAGAUAAAUAAUAAUAGCCCUGAGAUGUUUCUAACAUUUAAAUAAGAAAAAAAUCAAAUCGAAGUCAGCCUGCUGGAAAAGUGAUCACAUGGCAGUUGCAGUAACUUGUAUGGAAAGAGAAAAUGCAAUGAGCCCAGUUACUGCACUUGCCACUACCAUGCUGUCCAUGGAAGGAAUAAUCAGCAGUUCAGUUGUCACAAGCCGCCCUUGAAGAAAACGCAGCAAAAUAUUUUAAAAUGAAGAUAUUGCAGUCCCCAGAGCCAGUGAAGGUUUCUUUUGGUAAAAUGAAAUUGUGCCAUUGUCAAAGUACCCCGUAGUGAUGAGCACUGACUGGUUCACUGGCCACAUUUUAGUUCUUCAUAAUAAUAGGCCACAAAAGGGCUCUGUGGUUUGCCUCCAUGUGCACUGGCCCCUCCCCACCCCUAGGGGGCACUCAGUAGCUGCUGAGAAGGCCUGUCCACGAGGCUGUUGGAACCCCUCCAAUAAAUACUUAGAGGUAGUGUAUCUGAUGCUUGUUUUCGUGGAGAAAAUUGUAUUGGAGAACUUAAAACAUCACGAAUAUUUUUAAUAGGAUCCGCAGACACCCAAAGGAGAAGCUUGGUCUUUUCCAGGUAUUUCCAACUUGAGUUCAACCCAAAGCCUUUGAAAGGAAUGCAUUACCACAUGACCACAUGCUGAGACCCCAUGGGGUCUAACACGGGACCUAAGAAAGUCUCUGCAGCCAGAUAGUACAUGGUGUCUCCACAAAACUAGGCAUUCUGGAGAUUGCCCAGAAAGGGAUGUGAGGGGACCGUUAAGAUCUGUCUUGCUUAUCUCAUGCACUCACAUUCCUUCAGCCUCCUGGAGUUCCUGAUAAAAGGAAGCCAGGGUGUGGACAUUUUUUAGCUAUUGAUUUCCCAAUAGCUUGUGGAUCAGUUGUACACCCACACUUCCUUCUCUGCCUAAUUCCGUUUUUCUGGAAAAAGUAGUAUGCCCAUGUAUGUGUGUUUUUCUUAACACAGGUCCAUGAAAGUUUGGCUUCCUGGUUUGAUGUCUGUUGCGUGGCCUGGAAACCAGGGAGCAGCAACUAUUGAGAUGGUUUCUGUGUUCAGUGAAAAAUUCUAUUUCAUUGAGACAAUUUUUUCUUUAUCCACAGUAAUUUUUUGACACUGUCAUCAUGAAACUACCCUUAGGAAAAUAAGAUUACCUGCAAAAAAAAAAAAGAAAUGAGUUAUGGAAUAGGAACAGUUAUGUGAUGAUUCUGAAACUUUAACUUAGAGCUUCAUUACUUUAAGAAUGGAAAACAACCUCUGAGUUUGAUUUCCCAAAGUUUCAUAAAGCCCCUAAGCUCAUGAUUUUCAUCAACUCUUUGCCCACAUAGUCAUUUACCUCCACAGCCGUUUGUUGUCAUAGAAGGGGUGGUGGUGUUUGGAUUUGAUUUUUUUCAACUUGCAGUGAGAAAUAGGAUAGGUGACAAAACCUUACUUGUUUUCUUAAGACAAUUCAGUGCUUGAGCAUCUCUGUCAGAAAUGGAAUGAAAUACUGUUAGCCAAUUAGAAUUAUUUUAUGUAUUGUUAUUGUGUUUUGCUGAUUUUUAUAUGAAAAUAUAAUUAUUCAUUCUUGAUCUCUGGAAGCAAUCAUUAUUAUGAGGAUCAUUUUACUUUGGAAACACUUUCAUAAUAAAGAUAAGUAUUAAGAGUGCA